ACUAUGUUCUAAGUACUUUACAAGUAUGAACUCAUUUAAUUCCCUCAACUCUGUGAUAUAAGGUAAUUACUGCUGUUCUUAUUUCCAUCUUGCAGAGGGGAAACUGAGCACAAGAGAGGUUUAAUAAUUUGCAUAAGAUAACCUAGAGGUGGAGUUUGAACCCAGAGAGUCUGGCUCUAAAUUUUACAUUUUUUGGGGGGGGGGGUGGGGUGGGGCAGUGAAUGAAUUAAAAUGUAUAUAAAAUAAAAUUUACCAUUGUAACCACUUUUAAGUAUACAGUUCAGUGGCAUUAAGUACAUUCCCCAUUGCCUCUCCCCCCAGUGCCUGGCAAUCACCAUUCUACUUUCUGUUUGAGUGAAUUUGACUACUUUGGGUACCUCUAGGUAUUAUAAAUGGAAUCAUAACAGUAUUUGUCUUGUUGUGUCUGGCUUAUUUCACUUAGCAUAAUGCCUUUAAGUUUCACCCAUGUUGUUGUAUGUGUUAGAAUUUUCUUUUUUAUGGCGGAAUAAUCUAUUCUAAUAUUCUAUGUAUAUGCCACAUUCUGUUUAUCCAUUCAUUCCUUGAUGGACACUUGGAUUGCUUUUGGCUGUUGUGACUAAUGCUGCUUUGAGCAUGAAUGUACAAAUAUCUGUUUGAGUUCCUGUUUUUAAUUGUUUUGGGUAUACACUCAGAAGUGGAAUUGCUGGGUGAUCCUAUGGCAAUUCUGUUUAAUUUUUUGAGGAACUACUUUACUGUGUUUCACAGUGACUGCACCAUUUUAUGUGUCCAUCAGCAGUGCACAAAGUGCUAAUUUCUCAACAUCUUCACCAACACUUGUUAUUUUCUGUUUGUAUUUUUUUUUUGGUAAUGGCCAUCUUCAGGGGUGUGAUGUGGUGUCUCAUUGUGGUUUUAAUUUACAUUUCCCUAAUGACUAAUGGUGUUGAGCAUCUUUUCCUGUGCCUGUUGGCCAUUUGUUAUCUUUGGAGAAAUGUCUGUUCAAGUGACUCUGCAUUGUUUUUUUUUUUUUUUUUUUUUUUUGAGACAAGAGUUUCGCUCUGUCGCCCAGGCUGGAGUGCAGUGGCGCCAUCUCGGCUCACUGCAACCUCUGUGUCCCGGGUUCAAAUGAUUCUCCUGCUUCAGCCUCCUGAGUAGCUGGGAUUAUAGGCCCCCGCCACCAUGCUGGGCUAAUUUUUAUAUUUUUAGUAGAGACGGGGUUUCAUCAUCUUGGCCAGUCUGGUCUUGAACUCCUGACCUUGUGAACCACCUGCCUCAGCCUCCAAAGUGCUGGGAUUACAGGCUUGAGCCACUGCACCCAGUCAUGACUCUGCAUUCUUAACCAUUACCUGUGCUUCUCUUAGAUUUGUAACCUCUGAGAAUAGUGGAUCAGCUUUCUGGGCUGAUGAAGCCCUCCCUCAGGAGCUGGGCACUGGAUGAUCUAUUUGGUUGAAUAGUUAUCAUAGCCUGCACUUUGGUGACAUUUGUCAUGCAUGGACCUCAUGCAGAGAGGGAGGCACUGUUGUGAGUCCUGUUUUGCAGUUAGGGAAACUGAGAUAUGGAGAAGUUGAGUAUUUUAUCCAAGGUCUCAUAGCUAAUCAUUGGUGGAGCUAGGAUUUGAAUGGGUUCUGGAGUCCAUGCUAUACCUUACAGAUAUGGCCAGGGGGAUGGAGUAGUGAAGACCACUGCAGGCAGCAGAACCAGUGUGUGCAGAGGUUUGUAUAUGGUGGCUUUGGAGAAAGAACAGGACUUGGGUAGAAGUGGUCAGAGCCCAGCUUGAAUGGGGGUGACUUGAAGUUGGAGGAAGAGUAGGACAGGUCUGGAAAGGCCAGGAGCACGGUGAGGGUUUGGGGAGGAGGCUUGGUGCUUAGGGACCCUGUCCUUUUUUUUUUUUCUCUUCUCACAAGAUAUUUAUUAAUUACAAAGGGAAAAUAAUAACUGUACAGUGGAGAAAUUUGGCAGAUACUGCCUUAACCAAGGAAUUGGCUGAUCACUAAGAUUAAGACAAACUGUUGUUAUGAGUGGGUGUGGUAAUGUACCUAUAGUCCCAGCCACUCAGGAGGCUGAGGUGGCAGGAUUGCUUCAGCCCAUCUAUUUGAGGCUGCAGUGAGCUAUGGAGUGCACUCCAACCUGGGCAACACAGUGAGACCUCAUUUCUAAAAAAAGAAAAAAGAAGCCUUCUGAUACCAUGUACUAAGAAGGACACAACAUCACUUUUGUGUUAUUCUUGACAGAUAUGUUUAACUUUCUCUCCUUUCUUUCUUCCUCUCUUUCUUUCUUCUCUCUUUCUUACUGAUAUAAGAAAAAGCUUUAUACAUUUAAUAUAUACCUCUUGAUGAGUGGCCUUGGCCUUUGAGGUGGGCUGGGUCCAGAACAGCCGGUUGUUCAACGGUAUUUCCUCGUGUUUGGUCCCUGAAGGAAGAAAAUUGGAAGGGUGUGAUGGAGCUCAUGGUCCAGUGGGAGAGACAGGAAACGAGUUAUAUUUCCUAUCCUAGAUAAGAGUAUCUAAAAUGACAGGAUGUAAUGAGUGCUCGGAAGGGAAUAAAAUGGGUGAAAUUGCUGAGGGGGUCUCUUGGAGGAGAUGACAUUUGAAAUGAGAUCUGAAGGGGGUGAGGGAAGAGGUUCCAGACAGAGAACAGCUGGUGCAAAAGCCCUGAGGCAGGAAAGACCUUAUGUUCAGGAACAGCAGGGAGGGCUUUGUGGCCAGAGCAGGAAAGAGGUUGGAGAUAAGAUGGGAGAUUUGGACAAGGACUGAGUCCUGGAAGGCCUGAGGGCCAAGUGGGGAGCUUGGAUUUUUUUUUUUUUUUUUUUUGAGACAGAGUCUUGCUCUGUUGUCCAGGCUGGAGUGCAGUGGCUCAAUCUCAGCUCACUGCAGGGAGCUUGGAUUUUAUUGUAAGGGAGCCACAGGAGGGUUUAAACACAGCAGUAAUGAGACUUUAUUUCUGCUGGGAAAACAUUGCCGUUAUUGCCCCCAUUUUACAGCAGAGGAAACCGAGACUCAGAACCAUGACCAGGGAGUGCUUCCUAAGGUGGUUUCUCCCUCUGGGGUCCAGCCGACGAGGCAGUAGAUUCCUUGGGACUUCCUUGGGGGGCACAUCUGGUGAGUGGCCAAAGCCCAACACUGAAAACACCGUCUCUUCCACCUCCCCUCCCCAGAUGUGAGCCUGGGUUCCAAUCCUGGCUCUACCAUUAAUCAGCUGUGUAAUUUUGGGCACGUGGCCUUACCUCUUGGAGCCUCAGUUUUCUCAUCUGAAAAUGGGCAUAAUAAUAGUAGCCCUCACAGGGUAGGUGUGAGGAUUAAAUUAGUUAACAUUUUGUAGAGCUUAGAACAGUGUCUGGUACAAAGAAAGUGCUCAGAUGAGAUUUGUUCUUUUCUUUUUUGGCUGUAAGUUUAUUCAAUGUGAAAUAAUCCUCUCCAAUUUUAUUGAGGUGGCUGACCACGUCCACGACCACAUCUGCCUCUAAACUGGAAUUCGGUUGCUGACCCAGCCCCAGCCUCGGCUUUCUUGUCAGCACCAGGGGGCACAGAACACCGUCUCAGUGGCCGGUGUCCAGCUGCCUACUUUCUGCCCGGAUCUCUGGCUCCUCAUCUCUCCGGUCUCCGCAGACUAAAGCCCUCGGGAUAUGCAGCAGCCAUGCCUGUGCACACGCUGAGCCCCGGAGCCCCGUCCGCCCCCGCCCUACCUUGCCGCCUGCGGACCAGGGUCCCUGGCUACCUGCUACGGGGGCCGGCAGAUGGUGGAGCCCGGAAACCGAGCGCUGUGGAGCGCCUGGAGGCCGACAAGGCCAAGUACGUCAAGAGCCUGCACGUGGCCAACACCCGCCAGGAGCCUGUGCAGCCCCUGCUGUCCAAACAGCCGCUCUUUAGCCCUGAGACUCGCCGCACAGUGCUCACGCCCAGCCGCCGAGCCCUGCCUGGCCCCUGCCGACGGCCCCAGCUGGACCUGGACAUCCUCAGCAGCCUCAUCGACUUGUGUGACAGCCCCGUGUCCCCUGCCGAGGCCAGCCGCACUCCUGGACGGGCCGAGGGAGCCGGCCGUCCUCCCCCAGCCACCCCUCCGCGACCGCCGCCCAGUACCUCUGCGGUCCGCCGGGUGGACGUCCGCCCCCUGCCCGCCUCGCCUGCCCGGCCCUGCCCAUCACCCGGCCCUGCCGCCGCCUCCAGCCCAGCCCGGCCGCCGGGUUUGCAACGCUCCAAGUCGGACUUGAGCGAGCGCUUUUCUAGGGCAGCCGCUGAUCUCGAGCGCUUUUUUAACUUCUGCGGCCUGGACCCGGAGGAGGCGAGAGGGUUGGGUGUGGCCCACCUGGCACGGGCCAGCUCGGAUAUCGUGUCCCUGGCAGGGCCCAGUGCUGGGCCGGGCAGCUCUGAAGGGGGCUGCUCCCGCCGCAGCUCGGUGACUGUUGAGGAGCGGGCCCGGGAGCGCGUUCCCUAUGGCGUGUCGGUGGUGGAGCGCAAUGCCCGCGUGAUCAAGUGGUUGUAUGGGCUAAGGCAGGCUCGGGAGAGCCCAGCAGCUGAAGGCUAGGCGCCACUGGGCCUGGAAUUCGCCACAGGACGGAUCUUACAGAGGCAAGUGGUCCCUGGACCUCUCUUGCAUCCAUUCUCUAGACGGCCGUGUCAGAGGCUCCACCCUGUUGUGAACUUGGUAUGGAGGCAAAGGCUUAGAGGCUGGACCAGCAUUGUUGGGCAAGGACUGACUCUCCAAGGGUUUUGUUCUUGGCUUUGGACACCUGAGAACCCCCUCCUCCCCUCCCCCAAUACAAGGUUUUUGACAUGAGUGUACUCCUGCUUAGUUCCUCUUGUGGGGCUGCAUUUGCGGUGCUUUGCCCUCCCCACUGUGAGUGAGGGGCCAAGGGAUCUCCUCAAUCCUGUCUCCCCAGCGGCUCUGUUUCCUCCUUCCUUCCUUGGCCUCUGUCCUUUGCUGACUUCCUCUUCCUUACCCAGCAGAACUCACCCUGGGGUCGGGGCAGUGGGGAGGGGCCUAUCCACUGCUCUUCCUAGUCCUUGGCAGCUGGCCUAGGUGGGCAGACUAUAGGAGGGACUGGUUAGGAGUCUGCAUUGCUUUGACUUCCCUCUCCUUGGUUAAUAAACACAAAUGCUUGUUUCUCAA